ACUUCCUCUCAAGCUUGGCGUUUGUUUGGUGGGGUUACACGCGGGUUCAACAUGCGUAUCGAAAAGUGUUAUUUCUGUUCGGGGCCCAUCUAUCCUGGACACGGCAUGAUGUUCGUCCGCAACGAUUGCAAGGUGUUCAGAUUUUGCAAAUCUAAAUGUCAUAAAAACUUUAAAAAGAAGCGCAAUCCUCGCAAAGUUAGGUGGACCAAAGCAUUCCGGAAAGCAGCUGGUAAAGAGCUUACAGUGGAUAAUUCAUUUGAAUUUGAAAAACGUAGAAAUGAACCUAUCAAAUACCAGCGAGAGCUAUGGAAUAAAACUAUUGAUGCGAUGAAGAGAGUUGAAGAAAUCAAACAGAAGCGCCAAGCUAAAUUUAUAAUGAACAGAUUGAAGAAAAAUAAAGAGCUACAGAAAGUUCAGGAUAUCAAAGAAGUCAAGCAAAACAUCCAUCUUAUCCGAGCCCCUCUUGCAGGCAAAGGGAAACAGUUGGAAGAGAAAAUGGUACAGCAGUUACAAGAGGAUGUGGACAUGGAAGAUGCUCCUUAAAAAUCUCUGUAACCAUUUCUUUUAUGUACAUUUGAAAAUGCCCUUUGGAUACUUGGAACUGCUAAAUUAUUUUAUUUUUUACAUAAGGUCACUUAAAUGAAAAGCGAUUAAAAGACAUCUUUCCUGCAUUGCCAUCUACAUAAUAUCAGAUAUUACGGAUGUUAGAUUGCAUCUCAGUGUUAAAUCUUUACUGAUAGAUGUACUUAAGUAAAUCAUGAAAAUUCUACUUGUAACUAUAGAAGUGAAUUGUGGACGUAAAAUGGUUGUGCUAUUUGGAUAAUGGCACUAGGCAGCAUUUGUAUAGUAACUAAUGGCAAAAAUUCAUGGCUAGUGAUGUAUAAAAUAAAAUAUUCUUUGCAGUAAAAUAUUCCCUUUGUUAAUGUUAUAGAAGGGGGGAUACAAAAAGGAACUAACAAUUUGUAUGGCAGUGUCAGAUAUUUUUAUUUUAGUAUUUCCUGUUUUGGUUUAUUUGCAUCUUAGAAGAGCAUAAUGACAUUGUUUGAUGAAGCCUAAUUAUGCUGGACUGUUUUGACCUGGUUUAACCCUUCUGAUAGGUAGUUGUGGAUGCUGGGGAUGAGAACUGAAUAAUCUUUGCCUGGAGUGACACUACACUCUAGAAUUUCCACUUUGGAGAAUACUCAGUUCCAACUUGUGAUUCCUGAUAGAACAGACUUUACUUUUCUAGCCCAGCAUUGAUCUAGAAGCAGAGGAAUCCCAGCGCCUUUUAAAAGUUGUUAUGUGGUUUUCUUUUAAAAAGCUCCUGUUUUUGGAAAGUAGAAUUUAUGGGUACAACGUAUGUUCAUUAUUUGUACAUAAAAUAAAACCAUUUAAAAAGUAAUGCUGAUAUUUAUUCUUUAAAGGCACUAAACAAAGAUAUGAAAUAUUGAUGACCUGGAAGAAGAAAUCUUCCUCCACACAUCCCAUUUAAGUAGGAGAUACAUUUAAUUAAAGAGAAAUAGAUACUUAAUACUUAAUGUUUUGUGUUUUUACAUUGUUUACAGUUUUAAGUAUGUUAAAUACAUUAAGUAACGAUCAGUUUGCAUAAUGGUUUUUUUAGGGUAGAGUUUAAAAUCAGUAAUUCUUAGCCUUACAUAAUUAUAAAGUAAUGGCUCAUUUUUUGUUUCAGUAUUAGAUAGUAAAACUAAGGCUGUAGACCAGUCCCUGGACCAAGUGUUAGGAGACCUGAGUUCCAAUGUGGUUUUGCCUGGGUAUUCUUAUUUGUAAAUAAUAUUAUUGAUUGAAGAUUAGGGGAAAUGAUACAUGUGAGGAAAGACAUUUGUAAAAUUUCUUGGGUUUUUACUACAUACCGUAUUCAUUUUUUAAAGAAAUAAACAUUUUGAAAGUUA